GGAUUUGCAGCCUGAGGCAGAGCUCGGGGGCUGUCGGUGGGGACCUUGCAGGAGGGCACCCCAAGCCCGCCCGGCCCGCCCAACCCAGCCCCUGCGCGCAGCCCGGGCCGAGUAGGACCCCGCGCGCCCCUCGCUAUGGCGGCGCCCUCGCGGCUCCUGAUCCGCGGGGGUCGCGUGGUCAACGAUGACUUCUCGGAGGUGGCCGACGUGCUGGUGGAGGACGGCGUGGUGCGGGCACUCGGGCACGACCUGCUGCCUCCCGGGGGCGCUCCUGCGGGGCUGCGGGUCCUCGACGCCGCCGGCAAGCUCGUCCUGCCCGGAGGCAUCGACACACACACGCACAUGCAGUUCCCCUUCAUGGGCUCGCGGUCCAUCGACGACUUCCACCAGGGCACCAAGGCUGCUCUCUCAGGAGGCACCACCAUGAUUAUUGAUUUCGCCAUUCCUCAGAAAGGUGGCUCCCUCAUUGAGGCCUUCGAGACCUGGCGAAGCUGGGCUGAUCCCAAAGUUUGCUGCGACUACAGCCUUCAUGUGGCAGUGACGUGGUGGAGUGACCAGGUUAAAGAAGAAAUGAAAAUCCUUGUGCAAGAUAAAGGUGUUAACUCUUUCAAGAUGUUUAUGGCCUAUAAAGAUCUGUACAUGGUGACAGACCUGGAGCUGUACGAAGCCUUCUCUCGGUGCAAGGAAAUUGGAGCAAUUGCCCAGGUCCAUGCGGAAAAUGGAGACUUAAUUGCAGAGGGAGCAAAGAAGAUGUUGGCUCUGGGGAUAACAGGCCCUGAGGGCCACGAGCUGUGCCGCCCAGAGGCAGUGGAGGCAGAGGCCACGCUGAGAGCCAUCACCAUAGCCAGCGCUGUGAACUGUCCUCUCUACAUUGUGCAUGUGAUGAGCAAGUCUGCAGCUAAGGUGAUAGCGGAUGCAAGGAGAGAUGGGAAGGUGGUCUAUGGUGAACCCAUAGCAGCCAGUCUUGGCACAGAUGGCACUCACUACUGGAAUAAAGAAUGGCACCAUGCAGCCCACCAUGUCAUGGGUCCACCUUUGCGACCAGACCCCUCAACACCCGACUUCCUCAUGAAUCUGUUGGCUAAUGAUGAUCUAACCACAACAGGGACUGAUAACUGCACUUUCAACACCUGCCAGAAAGCUCUUGGGAAGGAUGAUUUUACCAAGAUCCCCAAUGGGGUGAAUGGUGUUGAAGAUCGGAUGUCCGUAAUAUGGGAAAAAGGCGUGCAUAGUGGUAAAAUGGAUGAAAACAGAUUUGUGGCAGUUACCAGCACAAAUGCAGCCAAAAUUUUUAAUCUCUAUCCAAGAAAAGGAAGAAUAGCUGUAGGAUCAGAUGCUGACAUUGUUAUUUGGGACCCAAAAGGCACAAGAGGAUGUAGAAGUUGUGUUGCAUUCUCUGACAAUGGAUCUGUAUAUAAAACCAAUAUGAAUUUACCACUUCAGUGCCUGGCAAAUGCCCGAGUUCACAUGGAAGAAAGGUUGGAGCAACGAGUUUGUUAAGCAGAGCUCUUAGAGAGAUGAAAUGAAGCCAAAAGAGUCACCUUUGUGUGUUCCUUCAUUCACAAAUUCACUCUGCACAGGAGCACCUCGGCAAGCCGCAGGCUGAGGGUCAAGCUUAUACAACAGCCACACCCUGCCUUUAAGAAGCUGACAGUCUAGGAGAGGAGAGGAGAUGUAAAGUCAAAUAUUCUCAGCCUAAGAAGGGAUGGGUUAAGAAUAUCACACGAGAGGCAGAAACAAGAUGCCUUAGAAAUUCAAAGAAGAAAGAUCAUUGUGGAGUUAGAGCAGUCAUCGACAUGAAAUCGUACGAGAGAGGUGAGUAGAUAACGUGGCCCUGUGAGUCAAGACUAAACAUGGAGGUGAGAUAAACCAAGGCAUUGACAGGGGGUUCUAGGAGGAAGCAGUUAAGGCUGGGGAUUGCACUACAGAGAGAACAGCUUCAGGCUGUAGAAGGAAAUGAGAAGGUGAAGAGGUUGUGGCUGUCUCCACUUUUAAUUGUGUUUAUCACAGACAGAGGCAAUUUUAAAUAGAGUUCACCUUGUAGAGAAGUGUUAUUUAAUCAAAUGAAUAAAUGAAUAUAUCUAUACGGUUUUUUUUUCUUCUUGCAAUGAAGGCCUCCCUUUUAAAUUUUACGUGCCUGAUUUUAACAUUAAAUGCAGGCUGGUAAUGUGCAGGAUUUUUGUCUCACACCAUUAGAUGUUGGCCCAAAUUUUCCUACAAAAUUUCCUUAAACAGUUUUAGCAAAAAUAAUUGCCCAGCCGUCUUGUUAGUAUCUAACAGGAAAGCAACAUGCAUUGCACCCUAGAUGCUGAAGGGGGCGCCCGCAGCCCGAGCACUGAGCUAGGCUGGCUCCAGCCAGGCCAUUCGAGCUGCUGGUUAUGCAAGAACAAGCCAGCCUCUGGAGAACGGAUGCAUUUGCUAAAGAUUUUUGGCUUCAUGGUACAUAGAUGUUUUCGUUUUUAAAAUUCUUGUUACUUAUUAAUGGCAUGUAGACGUAAGUAUGCUUGCCACACAAUCUGUAGCCUUAAAAAUGGACCACGUUAAAGUUACCAGGGGAGACCAGUGGAAAGAAAAGCAGGGCAGCCAUGCUUAUUUUUUCCUUUUAAAUCUGUAAAAAGUGAGAUGAUUCCAAGGUGAGGAAUUUGACAUAUGGUGAUGGAUGGCGAGAGAGAAUUGGGAGUGGGCGUAGUAGGGAAGGUUUGGACAUCCUGAUGAAAGAUUACCUAAGACGUCACUAGCCUGUAAAAAGUUCCUGCAAAAAUCAACUGCAAUAGCUCUUCUGUGUCAUUGCACAAUAAAGAACAAACUGCAUUUAGUGUAAAGGGAGCAUUCACCUUUUUCGGAAAUAAAGAGCCUGCUGUAUUCAGCCUGACAGCUCAUUGAACUGGUGUCUAUUGCUUAUGACGGAAGUAUGUGUCCUACUGCUUCACUACUUGGGUCAAAGUUUCAAAUUUAAGGACGUUUUCCAUAUCUGAAUGUCUGACCCAUUUCUGUAGAAGAUCUUGGUACUUAGAGUCAGGAGAAGAAAUCAGGAACAUGCUUUUCAUGUGAUGUAAAGACAGAAUCUUGUGGUGUCAUGUGGUCAAGACAGAGAUCAGCCAAAUUGGCCAACUUGUUAAAAAUCUUAUUAGAGAGAGUGACAUGUCAGUUACUUGCAAGCCCAUAGCUGCAGCAGUAAGUCAUGUUCUGGCAAUUUAAAACCAUCCUCGGAGCUUCAGUUCUUUGGUAUUCAUUAAAUAGCACUUAGUUACUAUGGUAACUGUCCCUUUUCAGUAUUUAUGAGCUACAGGAUAUCUCACAGAAUCUCAAGCACACAAACACACAGCUAACACAUUGUGUGUACUGGAACAUUUAAUGAAGACUUCUAGCUGGACCGUAUUCUGCCGAGCAGACAUAUUUUCAUUUAUUAUUUUUUAACUCAAUUAUGGCAGGCUUUGACCUUGAAUACACCAUUCUUGAAAGCAUUGUGCCAUCUUUCUUGCUUAAUUUCCUUCCUUUUCUCAUUGAAGAUAGAGAUAAAUGAAUUUAACUUUAUAUUCAGUGAAGAGUAAUGGCUUGCGGCUUAUGAUGGUGCCCUUCUGGAUUCUAGAGGGGGCCUUUUGUGUGAAAUAAAGCGGGGGAAGAAUGACUGUCAUCCUUGGGUAGUAGGGAUUGUAGGGCGUGGGGAGGGAGAAGAAAGGAGGAGUCAGGUACCCUUUGGCAAAGAGUGAUGGUUAUGGCUUAUUAGGAUAGCUACAUCACCAGUGACUGUUUCACAGAAGCUAUGAAGCAUUUUCCCUUGAAGUUGCACAUUGUGUAUCCUCUGACUAAUUUGUGCGUUAUAAUCCUCCUCCUCUUCCUCAAAGAAAGCGUGCACACACACACACACACACUCACAUGCACAUCAGCACAGCAGCCUGUGUUCCUGCUCAUAACAGUUGAUCGGCCUAAAGAUGCUGCUUUUCAUGCCUGUUUCUAAGAGUGUCUGUCACUAACGCGCCCGCCACUCCCCACACCCACAAGCAUCCCAGUGUGCAUUGUGUGGGUCUUGUCAUGGGUGCAUAAGUGGAAAUGAAUAUGAUUUAUGCCAUGAUUUGUCACUGUGAUGUCUUGUAACACAAUAUCAGGGCUGUACCAUGGUGUCAGGGCUGCUGGCUGAGGUGGUUCAGGUUGUGCUUUUGCAAAGUUACAGGGGCACUCUUCACAUCAUAGUUACCACAGAUAUAUGUGGAUAGAUAGGUAGCUAGAUAUAGAUACAGGUAGUAACUAUGCCAGUUUUCUAGCAUAUGAUAGCAAAGCACCUUGAGGAACAAAUAUCUGUUGCUAAUCCACACAAAAUCAAACCUGCCAUCUGGGCUAUUGGGGGGGAGCAGUACCAUAGAGUGAAGAGAAAGGCUUUGGUGAUAAAUUCCUAGUCUGCCACUUAUGAGCUGGGUGUGACCUUGGGUAUAUCAUUUAAUUUUUCUGAAUUUCAAUUUUUUUAUUUGCAAAAUGGGCAUGAUGAUGAUAUUUAUUUCCUAGCUUUGUUGUGAGUUUUAAGGUAGCAUCAUAAGAUGCUUGGAACAUAGUUAGUGUUCAGUAGCAGUUGGCAUGUAGUAGGUAGUCAGUUAGUGGUAAUAGAUAGUAGUAGUAGGUGGUCAGUUUGUGAAAUGAGUGGGAGCUCUUAUUAGCUAUAGCUGUGAGUCAGAAAUCUUUGUAUAAUGACUUAAUUCAGACAGGACCAAAAGAUACUAUAAUUAUAUUUCAUAUAAAAACUCUGUCUCCCAGGUUUCUUGCACACCUUUAAUUUUCACCACUAAAUUUCAGAAUGACUAAAAUUAAGAAGCUUGGAUGGAUUAUUUUGGCUAAGAUAGCCCGAGCCUCCAGAACUGACACCUUUUAAAAAUUAUUAGCAGUGAAACUGUUCAAACAAACCUCCUAAGAUUCAUUUUGUGGCCUUCAGAAGACAUUUGCUUUAAAAAAAAAAAAAAGUCUGGGCUAUGCAUGAAAAAAAGCUAACAUUGUUGAUUACAUAUGCAUACAAUUUUAACCACUCUUUAUUCCAAGUUGUUUAUUUAAACAUAUUUUUAUGCAACUGAACCUUUCAAGUGAACUAGAAAUGAUUUCUAGGGACUUUACUACUAAUAACUGCAUUUUCCCCCAAAUUAUAAAAGAAAAGCAGCUUAGAAAUGAAUCACAGUAACCCAUUCUAUCACUGAUCAUUUGGCUUGGCCAGAGUAAGCAGUUUAUUUUCAGCAUUAGCAUUGGGCAAAAAAUAAGCACCAAGCGAGGCUGUGUGAAAGGCAUAGGCUUUCCUAACUAAGCACCUGCUGUAUUUUUCUUCCUACCUGACAUAGAUUCUAUGUUUUUAUAUCUUUGACAUUUGCUUGUAUUAUUUACAACUGUAUCCCUAGGUUUAAGCACAGCUCCAGGUAUAUAUAGAAGCUCAAUAGUCAUUUGUUGAGUGAAGAAACCAGAUACUAAUGGACAAAUGUGUGAUUUAACAUUUUUGUCUGAACUUUAUCUGCCCAUGGAACUGGUUCAAGAGCCGUGUUUUACAUUCUUCCCCCCUUUGAA